AGGCUGCAGAGUAGGGAAGCGAGCGGCUGCCGAGGCACAGCGGCGAUCCGGCGGGGGCGGAAAAUGGCGGCGGCUUCGGAGGAGCUAAAUGGCGCCGGGACCCCUGGGGGGUGGGGUGGGCCGGGAGGUUGAGUAGAGAACUGGGCCAGAAGGAGUGGAGACAGUAAGGAAGCCCUACUUGUUUUCUCGUGGUGUUCUAUUUUUAGUUUUUAUUUUUGUUACGUUUUCGGUUUUGUUUUAUGGUCCAGCGUAGGAGAGGUAGGCUUGGGUGGGGUCGAGAGAGUGGGGGUGGGUCUCGACCCAACUUCCCCCCCUUUGCUUUUUUGUUCUUUUCCCUCGUUUGCGCUUUAGAUUCUUCUGUAAUUUUGCGGGGGUUCAGCCUUGCUCGGCGAUUCACGGCCCAGACAUAGAGAAUCGGGAUAGCUGGCCGAACCGUCUCUCUCAGUCUGACUCUCUUUAAAGAAGGGAUGUGGGCUGGGGCGCGGGGACAGUCCUGGUGGAGCACGGAAAAUGCGGCUGUAAAGUUGUAAUUACCCUAUUGUGCCGAGUUCCGAGAAAGUUCUUAAAAUUGUUAAGUCCACUUUGUUCUCUAAAAUGUACUUCGCUUUGAGAAUUUCUUCAGGGAGGUAUGUAGAAUGUUUUACCACAAUCUCCAGAGCAGAUUUGAGAGUAGAAGUGGCCAAGUGCCCUUUUGUGCAAUUGAAUGAUAGAGCAUAUGUCUUUAUAUAAAAUACUCGGUGUAGAUAAGGAAAAGGAUAAUAGUAUACAGUAUGAGUCAGGACUCCUCCCUUUCUCUCAUUGAAUUUGUGUAGUUGCUUUUUUCGCAACUCAUUCAUCUUUGUGUACCUCUUUUUAAUGUACAUGGAUUUGAUUAUGUGUGCCUCCUUUCUGACAGUCGAGGCUGCAUGUUGGGACGUCCUACAAAAUGCAUAUUCUGUGGAAUUAUUUUUUAAUAUGACAUGUCUUAAGCUUAAAGUGACGCCAUUUGGAAAAUUUUAAAUUAUACCUGUAUUUUUAAUUCGUGGGAGAAAACCAUUUGUAGCUUUUAAGCUCCAAAUACGAAAAUAUUCUUCCACUAUGUUGAAAGUAUUGCAAAAUCUGUUUUUUUCAGUUAAGGGUUUUCAUGUUUUUUCAUUACUUCAAAUUUCUUUAAGCUGGUUUUGAAAUUAUAUUUCAAAUAGCUUUCUGAGGAUUACUGUCUUUUAAUAACUUGAAUAAUUUGCCAUCACUUUAACAUUUAAAGAAUGACUAUGGCGAUACACCAAAAUCUUAUCUUUUUGCUCUUAUGGUGUACUUAGAGACAGGAUUUCAUGUAUUUGGUUAGGAUUUAGAAAUUCUGUUAAGAUUUAGAGAAAAAAGGUUAAAGCUACAUUCCUUAACGUUACAAAAAUUGUCAUGCUGAGAGAAUCCAAUUUGGUGUGAGAAUAAUUUUUUUCUUCCAUACAGAAAGCACAAAAACCAGCCUGAUUGUAUCUGGAAAAAACCAUUAUGUUACAGGUGUGAAAAAUACAUUUCAUGAUUGUGGUGAUUUUUAUCUCAUUUUAACUCUCGAUACUAGGUGCUUCUGUAUGCCACCAAACAAGCUAAUUUUUUUUCUUACUAUUUUAGUUGAUAGGCUCACCCCAAAAUAUGCUUUUGGGGACUGAUUUAGCACCUGCAUAUUCUGCGUGAAUCUCUUUAAUUGGUUGCAGUUGAGCUAAUGGUGGAGCCAAAAUGCUAUUGCCCUGUCUUCAUCAACAUUUAAUCAGUAAGUACUGGGCAUUGCAUCUUUCUUAGAACUUUAAGUUCAUACGUUGCAGUUAUAUGAAUACAUUAUUUUAUGUAAACAUUUUUCUGAGUGUUCAGGUUUUAGAAGUAUUUUGAGGGGAAGAAAUCAAAGUUUGGGCGUUAUGACUUGAGCUUUGAAAACAGCAUGGUUGGGAAAUGUUUACUGGUGGAGACUCAUAUCAAAAGUAGAUAGCUGUCCUCUAGUCCUUUUUUUAGAGAUCUCUUUUUUCAAUCCUUUAGUUAUCUCAUUACACCCCAGGGGUGCUUUAAAGGUGGGGAGAUAGUGUAUGUAUUUUAUAAGGUUAGUUUGAUAUCACUGGUUAGUAUUUAAAUAACAACAAAAAACUUGCCUUUACCUCCUCCGCAAAAAAUCUUACCUUUCUAUUAGCCUCAUUUAUCUCUCCAAAAUCUACAGACUCUAAUUUUUAUUAAUGGUGUAAUAAACUUACAUGUCCUGAAAAUAACAUCUCAUUAUUUUAAACAGUUGCCUUUGCCAUGCUUCAUUAAGUGCAUUGGCUUAAAUUAACACCUGUGAGGAUGAAUGGGAUAAUGUGAAACAAGUAUUCCUAAGGAUUUACUGCCUGGCACAUAGAUGUUAAAAUAUUGAGGGAGCUUAGAAGUGUUUUUGAAAGUAUUGACGUCUUGCAUCACUUGUAUUAAACACACAUCUGUCUGUUGCAAAGACAUCAAAAGCUUAGAAAGGAACAAAGUUUAAGGAGGGUUCAUUCUACUUUUUUUUAUAUCUUAUGUAGAGACUGCAUAUUUAACACUGAGGUGGUGUUCUGCCUUUCCAAAAUGGAGUUUUCCAUUUUAAUAGUCCAUUUUUUUUCUUACCACCAUCAUAUUUUUCCUAUAUGAAAGGAUUUCCUAGGAAUUGAUAUACUUUUAAAUGCUUUGCAAUUGCAGCUCCUUUAUGUCUCCAAAUGAUACAAGAAGACCCGAGAAAGUGGUAAACUAAAUGAUUUUUAUUAAAGUAAUUGCCAAAUAUUAAAGAUAAAAUAUGGAUAGUUACCAAAUGUAUGUGGCGUUUGUUUACUUUCAUGUCAUUUCUCCGUUUAUCUUGAUGGUGCUUUCAUUUUGUGAAGAAAAUUCCUGUAAUAGAAAUCACAAAUAGAUUUUGUGUUUGCUUUGAUUCUAUAAAGGUAGAUAAGUUUAAAUAAAAGGAGGAACGUGGUUGUGUCUCCCCCACCCCACCCCCGCCCCACCCAAGUUUGUAGAAAGAUAAUCCAUUCCAUGACUGAGUACUAGAAAUAAGUUGUCAGAGAAAAGCACACUGGAGAGCUCAUUAUGAACAGUUUAAUUUUCUAUCAUUUCAUAUAUUUAAAUGUCAUUUUGAUUAUGUACACUGUUAGGUCAUUCUUCCAAGCACCAGUGGUCAAAGCUGAUUCAUUCACUUCCCAUCAGGUGUUACGUAUCAGAAAUGCUCAUUAGGUUUAUUUUAGUGCCGGUGUAUAUUUUAGUAUCUAAUGAGUAAAUGUGCUUUAAAAAUUAACUUCACUGUAAAUCACAGGUGUCUGGUGAUACUGUAUAUGUCCAUGUAAAGAGCCUCUGAUGGUGCCUUGUAGAAAAGUACUCAGUUUUGAAAGGAUGAAAUCUUUCAAGUGUGGCGAAUAACACAUUGUAAGCUCCUGAACCAUGCAUGAAGUGAAAAAUAACAUUUUUGCUUUUUGAAUAAGCAAUAUAGUUUUAUUGUCAAACCAGAUAUGAAAUGCUGCACCUUAAAAUCCUUGCUAUUAAGUAAUCCUCCUUACUCAAGUAAUAGUGACAUUGUUUUCAAUAGUUGGUAAUUGAAAUCAACAAAGCCUGCUAGAAUAGACUCCACUAACAGCUCUGUUGACAUUUUUAUGAUAUAUAAUCAUAUUUUACCAUCUUAAAACCAAGCCAUAGUAAACAUUAAUUAGGUACCUUAAUUGAAUAUGCCUUAUGUUCAUUUAUGGCUCUGCUGCUCAAACUUUUCCACAAAGUAUAUAGAGGAACAAAUCCCACGGGGCCUGGCACCAUAGUCCAAAACAUUCUUCUUCAAGUGUGUAGUGUUCCUAUUCGUAUCUUGAAUAAAGUUUGUGCUUAUGAAGAUGUUAUGCUUAUUCUAUGACCUUACCUCUUGUCUGACAGCCCUCUGUGUACCCAUGUUUAGGAUGUAUGAAUUUGUUACCUAUUAUCUUCCACUAAGAUUUUCUACUAAGCAGACUUUCAUUAUUUCAAAAUAAACAUAUCUUAAAAUUUAUCUUCCAAAUUCCUUAGACGUUACUAAGCAAAUUCUCUUUUAAGUAGUUUUUAAAGCAUUAGUUAUACAAUGAUAGAGUAAUAGUCCAUUUGGAGUUUUAUAAUAACAUAGCUACAAAAAUGUUGAGUAAUAGGUACGAAUUAGAUAAAUUUAGAUCUAUGUGCUCAUUCAAAAUGUAAAGUAGUAAUGAUACUGGAAAAUGCUCCUGAUACAGUAAGUACAAAAAAGUGUGACAGUAUGAUCUUGUGAAAACAGUAAAAGAUAGGCAUGCUGAUAACAUGGGUAGAAGACUUGCAAAUCACAUAGAAAGAACAUGAAUGAUUUUUCUUAUACUGUAUUGGGUCAGGAGAAAAAAACAUCUGAAAACUGUCCUUACUGCCUUAUUAGUUGAUCUAUGCCAGAGACUGUUUCUCAGCCUGUGUUUCUCAGUCUUUAACUCACCUAACAAAAUUGUGGUGCUAUAUGUUCUGUAGCUUGCAAGAUUUCACAGUAUAAAGUGAGUGUAUUAAAAUAGGGAAUGUUUUAUAUCAUGUGGUCUCAUCCCAUGUUCCAUUUUAGAAUCACAGCUCCAAGCCUCUAGGGUCAGCAAAUGUUGGUUCCUGUGCUGCUCAUGAUUGCCACUAAUAGCAUCUAAACUCUUUCAUACUUGUAUCAGUACUGUAGUUGGAAAUGAGUAUACAGCUGUUUACAGAAUUAGCCCCCAAAACUGGGAAGAAAGGUGACUUUAUUCCUUGAUUCUGGUUUUUAGAAGAUAUUCAACACUUAAAUGCCCAGAAAAAUCAGGACGAUAGGUAGACUCAAUUGAUGGAAAUACCAGUCUAAGAUAACCCAUUGGAUAAGAACUUUACAUCAAUACUGAAAGGAAGAAUAGCAUGAAUAACUCAUUUCUUUAAUUGAAUUCUGUGUUAAAUAACAGAUCCAAGAGUUAUUUCUUUAUGCUUAUCCCUUUUCGUUCUUCCAGGCUAUAGUAUAUUAAAUAGGUUCAUCUUUUUCAUUGGGAGCUAUAAGGUUAUAUUAUAAUGAAGACACAAUAACUCCAUUAUAAGAGUUUUGUACCACACUUAAGGUUAUGUGUUUUUUUUUUUAAGCCACCAGAAUGGUUUUAUUUUUGUCAUUGACAACAUGUACAAACCUGCAAUUGUAUAAUUGUUUUGUUUGGUUUUUAAAAUACUAAGUACACAUUAAAAGUAUGUUUUAAGAAAUAUGAUGCAUUAAAGAAGUUCACUGUAAACAUAAUUCUCAAUGUAUUUUCCUGCCUUGUUUCAUGCAUAAAUAACAAUCUAAGUAGUCAUAAAUAAAACUAUCAACUUUUGUGGCCCAGAAGUAUAUACAAAUUUUGAAGUUUGGCAGAAGGUGUUCUGUAUGGUUUUAUAAAUUAAAACGCACAGCAUUUGUAUUGAUUAUUAAUGAAAUGACUUAUCCCAAGUCCUUAUUGUAUCCCAACCUGUUCUGUCAAUAAUAAACGUUCCAAUGUACUUGGUAAAGAUGCCACAUGUUUAAAAACUCAAUGAUUAAAAUAAUUCUAAAAGGUAAUUUAAAUAGUACUCAGUCUUAUUAAAACCACUUCAGCUUGUCUGAAAAAAUGCUUCUAAGGAGUGAAUUCUGUACCAUUAUUUAAAUGGCAUCUAACAAAAUCUAAAAUUUAAGGAAUAAAUCAAAUACAUUUUAGUCUUGCAAAAAAACUUCAUUGAGAUUGUUACAGGAACAGAAUGCUAUCCUAAGUUUUCUAAAAUUUAUUCUUGAGUCAUCAAUGAGUUAAAACUUUAAGAGUUAUAAUAAUUUUAGAAAGCCAUAAUUCUUGAUGCAGAACAUGAUUAGUUUUUAAUGACCAGAAAUUAUUUCUUCAGAAAGCAUUAAAUAACUGUUGAAACGUACCACCUAUCUAGUGAUUUAUCAAGUAAUCACUCAAGAUUUAUUAAGUACACAUUUAAAUUUUAGGUAAUAAAAGUCAACUGGAAUUUUGUACAUUUCACUGUAUUUCAUUUUAUACUUUUUUUAGGUCUUCAUUUAUAGGGUAUAAAACUUAGAAAACAUUCUUAACCAGUGUCUUCCUUAGAGUUAAAUGAUUCAAACAACAAGUAAUGCUAAGCUAAAUGCUGUCGUUAAUACUGAAACCUAAGUUUCUAAAAGUUGUAUUUUUCAAUCAAUACAAAAAUGAUCUGGCUCACUGUAAACUGCCUAACUUUAAAAAACUAUUAUUUGUUAAACAGCAGAUUACAAGAAAUGUUUCCCCUGUUCUUUUAAAAAACAAGAUUAUGAGAUACAUAAUCUAAAUAAAAAUUUACAGAUGGUGGUUGAAAUCCUGUCAACUUUCAGCCCAGUGUAACAAAUUCCAUAGUUAUGCAUGAAUAAUUCAAAAUUAAAGUUUUUAAUGGAAAUGUCAGUAAGGCAUAUAACUACAUUUGUCAGGCACAUGAUAAGACUAGAAAAUUAAAGCUAUCAAAGCUAUAAAUAAGGAGUGCAUAAAUAACAGCAAUGCCAAAACAUUAGGGCUGUUAAAAUUUAAACACAUCUGAUAGUUCUUUCUGUAAGCCACUCUCCACUGAUAAAGCUAUGGAUAAAACUUAAUUCCUUGCACAGCUUUCUAAUAACUGAUGAUAAAGCUGAAUUCCUUGUUCAUAAAGCUGUACACCAAUAGAAUUUUCACAUCUAUUCAAAAUUCUUGAAAUCUCAAGCAGAUCGUCCAUGGUUUUCCUAACUGCAUUUGGAUUUGCUGCUACCCUCAGGUAUUUUUUUCUUUAACGUGCUAAGGUAUUGUGCUAUUUAAAGAUACACAGCAAAUGAUGAAAACAUGCAAAAAUGCCACUUCAGUUAAAAUGGCUGUUAAAAUUGUGUUUAUUUUUCUUCUGUAUCUUCUCGUUUUUAGUGUAAAAAUAGUACAUAUGGUAUAACCCAUUACAAAGAAGGAAAAUUGAGCUGAUGUGCAGUCAUGUGUUGCUUAAUGACAGAGUUCUGAGAAAUGCAGUUUGGGUGAUUGCAUGUGAGCAUCAUAGAAAAUACACAGACCUGUACAGCGUGUUACUGUACUGAGUACAAUGUUAACACAAUGAGUGUUGCGGAGAUAGGAACAUGGGAGAGAAACAAUCUGGGUAACAUGAAAGUGAUGCUGGUUGCUAAGGGAAGGCAACUUGAUUCUGUGGGAAGGGCUGUAGCUGAUCCAUCCGUUGUCUAGAUUUGAGUAUGAGCACAGUGGAAGAGGAUUCUGACACAGUAACAGUAGAAACUGUGAACUCUGUGACUUUGACUCAGGACACAGAAGGGAAUCUCAUUCUUCACUGCCCUCAGAAUGAAGCGGAUGAAAUAGACUCAGAAGAUAGUAUUGAACCUCCACAUAAAAGGCUUUGUUUGUCCUCUGAGGAUGAUCAGAGUAUUGAUGAUUCUACUCCUUGCAUAUCAGUUGUUGCACUUCCACUUUCAGAAAAUGAUCAGAGCUUUGAAGUGACCAUGACUGCAACCACAGAAGUAGCAGAUGAUGAGGUUACUGAGGGGACUGUGACACAGAUACAGAUUUUGCAGAAUGAGCAACUAGAUGAAAUAUCUCCCUUGGGUAACGAGGAAGUUUCAGCAGUUAGCCAAGCAUGGUUUACAACUAAAGAAGAUAAGGAUUCUCUGACUAAUAAAGGACAUAAAUGGAAGCAGGGGAUGUGGUCCAAGGAAGAAAUUGAUAUUUUGAUGAACAAUAUUGAACGCUAUCUUAAGGCACGCGGAAUAAAAGAUGCUACAGAAAUCAUCUUUGAGAUGUCAAAAGACGAAAGAAAAGAUUUCUACAGGACUAUAGCAUGGGGUCUGAACCGGCCUUUGUUUGCAGUUUAUAGAAGAGUGCUUCGCAUGUAUGAUGACAGAAACCAUGUGGGAAAAUAUACACCUGAAGAAAUUGAGAAGCUCAAGGAGCUCCGGAUAAAGCAUGGCAAUGACUGGGCAACAAUAGGGGCGGCGCUAGGAAGAAGUGCAUCUUCUGUCAAAGAUCGGUGCCGACUGAUGAAGGAUACUUGCAACACAGGGAAGUGGACAGAAGAAGAAGAAAAGAGACUUGCAGAAGUGGUUCAUGAGUUGACAAGCACUGAGCCAGGUGACAUAGUCACACAGGGUGUGUCUUGGGCAGCUGUGGCUGAACGAGUCGGUACCCGCUCAGAAAAGCAAUGUCGUUCUAAAUGGCUCAACUACCUGAAUUGGAAACAGAGUGGGGGUACUGAAUGGACCAAGGAAGAUGAAAUCAAUCUCAUCCUCAGGAUAGCAGAACUUGAUGUAGCUGAUGAAAAUGACAUUAACUGGGAUCUGUUAGCUGAGGGAUGGAGUAGUGUCCGUUCACCACAAUGGCUACGAAGUAAAUGGUGGACCAUCAAAAGGCAAAUUGCAAACCAUAAGGAUGUUUCGUUCCCUGUCUUAAUAAAAGGUCUUAAACAGUUACAUGAGAACCAAAAAAACAACCCAACGCUUUUGGAGAAUAAAUCAGGAUCUGGAGUUCCAAACAGUAAUACCAAUUCCAGUGUGCAGCAUGUUCAGAUAAGAGUUGCCCGCUUGGAAGAUAAUACAGCCAUCUCUUCUAGCCCCAUGGCAGCAUUGCAGAUUCCAGUCCAGAUCACCCAUGUUUCUUCAGCAGACUCUCCUGCUACCGUUGACUCAGAAACAAUAACACUAAACAGUGGAACACUACAGACAUUUGAGAUUCUUCCCUCUUUCCAUCUACAGCCCACUGGCACUCCAGGCACCUACCUACUUCAAACAAGCUCAAGCCAAGGCCUUCCCCUAACUCUGACUGCUAGUCCCACAGUAACCCUGACAGCUGCUGCUCCUGCUUCUCCUGAACAGAUUAUUGUUCAUGCUUUAUCCCCAGAACAUUUGUUGAACACAAGUGAUAAUGUUACAGUGCAGUGUCACACACCAAGAGUCAUCAUUCAGACUGUUGCCACAGAGGACAUCACUUCUUCCAUAUCCCAAGCAGAACUGACAGUCGAUAGUGAUAUUCAGUCAUCUGAUUUUCCUGAGCCUCCAGACGCCCUAGAAGCAGACACUUUCCCAGAUGAAAUUCAUCACCCUAAGAUGACUGUGGAGCCAUCAUUUAAUGAUGCUCAUGUAUCCAAAUUCAGUGACCAAAAUAGCACAGAACUGAUGAAUAGUGUUAUGGUCAGAACAGAAGAAGAAAUCUCUGACACCGACCUUAAACAAGAGGAAUCACCCUCUGAUUUAGCCAGUGCUUAUGUUACUGAGGGUUUAGAGUCUCCCACUAUAGAAGAACAAGUUGAUCAAACAAUUGAUGAUGAAACAAUACUUAUCGUUCCUUCACCACAUGGCUUUAUCCAGGCAUCUGAUGUUAUAGAUACUGAAUCUGUCUUGCCUUUGACAACACUAACAGAUCCCAUACUCCAACAUCAUCAGGAAGAAUCAAAUAUCAUUGGAUCAUCCUUGGGCAGUCCUGUUUCAGAAGAUUCAAAGGAUGUCGAAGAUUUGGUAAACUGUCAUUAGAAUAAUUCUUAGAAAUAGGCAGUUCAAGCAAAGAAGGCACACUGUUAAUUACAACCUCUUCAAAGAAAUAGGAGCAACCCCCAAGAGGCUUAAUUUACCAAUUUAAAUAGCCACAGUCCUUAAGCCACACACAUUGUUGCUGCUAUGACUUUUUACCUCCUUUAAACACAUCAUCUGAGGUUGAGUUUUAUGACAGUAUGUAGUUGAGUGGAGGCUGGGAGUUUUAAGCAUAAAUCCCUGUUUAGUGUUACAUGGGAAUAAGGAAUUUCAUUCACUUCAGCCACUAAGAAAAGUUUAGAAUCACGAAAGCUUAACUGCUGUGGUUUAAAGUACAGUUUCUCUAAAGAUCAGACAUGGCACUGUCUCCUCUCAAGCCUGGUUGUAGUUCAGAUGAGUCUUUUCAACAUGGUCUUCAACAUGGUCUAGAGCUUACCAGUGAUCUUCUGAUCUUCAAGAAGACUAAGUUUGAGACUUGACCAGCAUACAAGUAUAGAGACCUAGGAGGUGGUCUUGUGGUGGUACAUUUGGUUAACCCAUUGCUGGCAGUGGGAGCUGAUUUAGGCAGGGUAAACAGGAAAGCAUUAAAAGUUAAAAUUCACUACAGGUUUUUUGUUACUUUUAAAGGGAAUAUGGAUAAGCAUAGUAACAAAACCCACCAGAAUCUAAGCAGUUUUCACCCCCUCAGAAACCACUGUCAUUAGUUUACAAAGUUAGCACUUUGAAGUAAAACUAAAUGAGGAAGGAAGUAAUGUUACCUAUCCUUGAUACCAUGACCAUUUAUUAGAUGUUUUGCUAUAUAAAUUACCGAGAGAAUAGUUUGUCAUCCACUUAGUGUGUUAGCUGGUGGGGUACAAUAUAACCUCUCAUCUCAGGCUAUUUUAAAAAAACAAUAUUUGCUUCUAUAACAAAAGGAAACAAAUCUAAGAAUCAUUCCUGUACUACAGAAGGGUUAAGGCAAAGGUAGCCUUUUGGGCUUUUUAAUGAAUAUGACCCCUAUAGAAAAGUCAAGAAAAAAAAACCCUUGUAUAAAUUAUUUUAUUUAUUAUUGUAAUUAGAUCUUCACAAAGUUGUCUUUUCACUGUGUUUUGUCAACGUGAAAUUAAAUUGUAGUUAUAAGCAAAAGUUGGUUGCCUAGGGAACAAUUGUAUAUUCAGUUUAACAGAAAUAAAAGAAUAUUUGUCUUAA